CUCCAUCUCACCUGUCUAUACUCAGUGACGUUUAACAGUUGGCUCUCCAAGGAGAAAAGCCUGAUAGGUAGUACUUGCCAAUUACCAUGGUGUAAAUCCUUCUACCAAGACUGAUUUUAAUUUACCCACUCUGAGCUGGGAAGAGAUGUACAGUAGUGCAUUAUUAUAUAGUAUUUCCCUCAUACAGAUAUAAUAGGUGUAAAUAAUCUCAUGACCAUAAACAAUAGUAAAAUACAGUAAAAUAAUUAGAAAGUGAUGAGUUUUAAAUAUUUACUAUCACUUUAAAAAUAUAAUUUUAAGUUUAUAUAAUUUAAUUAUUAAAAUAGUGGCUGUAGUUAACAAUCAGCUCCAAAAUUUACUGAAAAUGUUACAACCAACUCUCUUGAGCCAGUCCAUGCCUGCCCUGGCAUACCACUGUAUGUGUGUUUGUAUCUUUGAAAAUAGCACUUUAGCAUCCACCGUCGGGUGGGUCCUACUACCAAGCUACUGAAAUUGUCUCAUGGCAGUGUUACUUACCAGUGCCUGCUGUGGGCCUUUUGCUAUGACUGGUCUAACAGCUACAUGAAAUAUGUUGGUUUUAUGGACUUUAUAAUCUAGGCAGUGAAGGGGAACAUACUUAUUCAUCUGUCCCACCCAUUAGUCCAUCUGUCUAUUUGUGCAUCCCCCACCAUUUAAUCAUUCAUCUCUUUUUUUCCACCCACUCAUCCACGCUUCCAUCCAUCUGAACAUUCACCAGUCUGUUUACCCAGAUCUUCCUCCCUCCCUUCCUCCAUCCAUUUUUACUUUCUUCCCUUCAUCCAUCUACCCACCCACCAGUAAAUCAAUGAGUGCUUGUUUAUCACGCUCCUGUAGUGAGUCAGGUGUUGUGCUUGUGUUUUAAAUAUGUAUAAAACUUGUUCUCUACUCUAUAGAAGCUCCUGAUUGAGAGAGAUGUGAGUAGUUACAACAGCCAGGAUAAAGGCAGAUGCAAAGUGCUUUCAGAGGUGAGAAGAAAAAAUGAGUAAUUCUGUUAGGAGUAGGCAAGCAGGUUGGGAAUGGCUUUACGGGGACUGACAUUUACUUUGCUUUUCAGAUUUCAAGUGGGCAUUUCCUAGGUGGUGGGGGAAGGGCACCCUAGGCAGAGAGGGCAGCGUGUGAAAAGGCACAGAGGCUGGGGAGCCUGUCCCACAGGGUUGUUUUAAUUGCCUUCUCUGAACUCCCAGUUCACACAGAAGCCUGGCAGGCAGGGUUGGCUUCUAGGAGAAGGGGGAGUUCUGCUAAGUGGAGGGGACCAGGGAGGCACAUGGGACCAGAGAACCUGCCCAUAGGGACUGAGGGUUAGAGUAGCAUGGAACUGUGGUGUGAGGGAUGCCACCAGCUGAUGCACUUGAAGGCAUUUUUUAGGGACAUGGAGAUGACGGAAAUAAUGAAAGGAAACUAACAGUAAAGGCACCACCUAUGUGCUAAGCACUUUACAAACACUGAGUCCCCACAAUAGACACAUUAGUCUUUACAACAGAUAAUAGAGUAUUAUCCCAUUUUACAAAUGUGGAAACUGAGGCUUAGAGAGUGGUGGAUUGCCCAAAGCCACAAAGCCUCAGUGUAGUCUGUGUCUAAACAUGUGCAGAGUUCUGCGGAUCUAAUCUCUCAUUCUAUCCCCUCAACAAUCCUGAGAUGUUAAGCAACCUGUCAGACGUCAAUCAAGACUCCAAGGUCUUGGCUGGGCAUGAUAAGGCCAGACGUCCUAGGGAGCCUGUGCCUAGAAGGUGGAGCUGAGGUGUUUGGCUGGAUGAGGACAGCUGACAGUCCCUCUGUCUGCAGUCUGCAGGUGAGGGGAGCUAUGGAAGUUUGAACAACUGGAUGGAGGCUACGACUUAAAAGGUCAGUUUGUGACCAGACCAGAGAGAGGCCUUGUAGUGGCCCAGGUUCUCACUACCCACUUAGGUGUGGCUGCCCUGUCAGGCAGUGGCACUGAUUGAUGUCUGCUGUCAAUAAGUGUGCUUGCAGCUGCUCCCAAGCCUUUCUGCAAGGGCCUGAUUGCCAUCAUACCAGAGGAAGCACUUGGAAGGAGAAUGCAUCUGAUUAGUCAGUAACUAAUGAACACAGGGAGAAAAAACACUUGAAAAAUUCCUAGCAGGGCUCUGACAUUUGGCUUUCUGGCAGCUAGUAGAGAUUGUGGUUAAAAGUUGUUCAGAUCUGGGUUCUAAGGUUGGAGAGAGUGGGAGGAAGUGCUGUAGAAAGGGACUCAAUUUUGUUCUGAAGUGACCAGUAAGAAUUCCAGUUUUCAGCCUCACUUGGACUUAUUUGAUUUUCCAGGGAGUUUACAGGGAGAGCUGGAGACAUAUUUUGCCGUGGUGAGAGGUGGUAGCCGUGAGGCUGGUCAGCUUGAGUCAGAGGGAGCUUCACCUUUUAUUAGCUAUGUGAUCCUGUGCACCUUAACCUCUUGGAGCCUGUUUUCCAGUAUGUAAAAUGGGGCUGAUCAUCCAUUCAACAACUGUUUAGUGAACACCUACUAUGUGACAAGGGCAGCUCUAAAUGUUUGGUCCUGGCGUAUUGGAGCUGUUACUCCAGUGAGUGAGAGAUUGUAGAUGAGAUCACAGGUACAAAACACCUGGCACACAGUAGACAGAAGCACAGACUUCCUAGCACAUAGGGGAUAGUGAUCAAAUGAGGAAAUGAAUAGGAAAGUACUUUCUAUUAUAUGAAGUAUGAAACGGGGCAUUGAGAGGAAGAUCGAGGGCCGGGCGCAGUGGCUCACGCCUGUAAUCCCAGCACUUUGGGAGGCCGAGGCGGGCAAAUCACGAGGUCAGAAGAUUGAGACCAUCCUGGCUAACACGGUGAAACCCCGUCUCUACUAAAAAUAUAAAAAAUUACCCAGGCGUGGUGGCAGGCACCUGUAGUCCCAGCUACUUGGGAGGCUGAGGCAGGAGAAUGGUGUGAACCCGGGAGGCGGAGCUUGCAGUGAGCCGAGAUUGCGCCACUGCACUCCAGCCUGGGCGACAGAGCGAGACUCUGUCUCAAAAAAAAAAAAAAAAAAAAAGAGGAAGCUCGUAGGCACUGAAUGUGGGUUAUCCUGAGGUGUGGAUGAAGCAGGCACCUACACCCUCAUCCUUAAAAUAUCACCUGUUUCUCCCAGCACGUUCACCAGCCUGGUUUAUUUUUUUUAAAGGCAUAGUUUCAAAACCUCUGGAGGUGCUGUGUACACCCACCUGUGGCUUGUUCAUGUUCCCAUCAGACAAUGUCACCAUUGUGUGGCUGUGGUGCCAUUCACAGGCAUGACCCAGUGUCUGCUGCUGCAUGGGGUCCCAGAUCAGCCUUGCACACCACAGACUGGAAGAACUGGGGGACUUUGCCCCUGAGUGUUUCCCUACUUGGAUACAGUCCUGCAAUGGUAACUCAUGUUAUAUUGGCAUUUUUGUUUUUGCUACAGUGAGAUUGUUGUGAAACUAUGUUUGCUUUGUGCUUUGGUGACAUGGGAAAGUGUCAGCUCCCCUCUUGGGUCUGUUAGUCCUGAGUGACAAGUGGCCAGCCCUGUUCCCAGGGUCAGGGGAAACACUGUGAUGGGUAUUAUGCAAUAUGCCUUUCCCUCUCUCUCUGCUUUUUCCGCACUGCUGUAGCACUUGACCUUCUGUGGUAGUGGUUUCUGUGUGGGCCCCUCAGUAACAGUGUGGCAUCAUUAGGAGCCAGUUAUUGCUUUCAAACCCCGCGUACUUGUCACAUAACAUUGGGAAAGUCACUUUGCCUCUUUGAGCCUCAGUUUCCUCAUCUGUAAGAUGGGGAAAAUAAUAUCUCCCACAGAGGUGGGUUGGAAACUGAAGGAAUCCCUUGUUUGUAAAGUGUUCACGUUGCAUGGCAUCAUCUUCAUGGUAAUUAUAAUCACAGCUAACCUGUUGAGCCCUUGCCGUGUGUCAGGCAUUGGUAGAUUAUCUCAUUUCAAUCUCACAGUAACCAGAAUGGGUGAUCCAUUUUACAGAUGAGGCAACUGAGUCUCAGAUAGGGUAAUUCUGGGCAAGUUACUAAAACUAUCAGGAAAUGCUUGGAGCAUGUUUGGAACUAAAUUAUCUGACUCUAAGAAGUGUUCUCUUAAUGAUUUCACCGUAGACAUUUGGCAGAUGGUAGUUACUAUCCUACAUAAGACUGGAGCAAGCAUUGCCCCCUGCACAGGUAGAUGCUCAGGCAGUGUUUUCUUCAUGCACCAAGGCACGCAUGCAGCUCUAAGCUACUUAACUUGAUAUUCAGAGGCAAAGUUAGGAGUAGGGAUAGUCCCAGGAUGUGGAAAAAGAUGAAAAUCCUAAUUAAUGAGAAGCUGUGCCACUCUUGCUGGUCACUUGCUCUGUGUGAGUAUCCCUUUGAAACAAAGGCUUCUAGGUGGGCAGGUAUUAGGGUUUAUCUUUGUUUGGUGGUUGUGCAGGCAAGUAGGUUACUGCAGAUAAAAAGAGAAGAAACCAGCAGAUGGCUCUUCCCCUCCCCCUGCUGCCUUCUUCUGGGUCCAGACAGGGAUUUAUACCCUUUGGUAUAAAUGUUCAUGUUAGCCAUAUUACAAAACAUAUGUCAAGAGCAAAGGCUGGCAAUACAAUUCCUCAUAUGCUCAGAUGGGGAAUAGAGAACCCAUUCACAUCUCAGUGCUCCUGGAACCCAGCUUUCUAGGAGUCUUACCUGGCUCAAGAUCAGCUGAGAACCAAAGAGCCUUCCCUGCUGUACCCUGGGGCAGCUCAAAGGCGUGUCACAAAAUCCUUCUACUUAUGGGUUUUCCUUGAGGGAAAAGUUCCAGCAUGGCUCUUGCUUAAACAGUAUGUGCUCUUACUUUAUACAGAGUUUUGUUUGAGACAGGGUCUCGCUCUGUUACUCAAGCUGAGUGCAGUGGUGAUCAGGGGUCACUGUAGCCUCGACCUCCUGGGCUCAAACAAUCCUCCUGCCUCAGCCUCUUGAGUAGCUGGAACCACAGGCACAUGCUACCACACCUGGCUAAUUUAUUUUAUUUUGAGAUGCAUUUUCACUUUUGUCGCUCAGGCUGGAGUGCAAUGGCGUGUUCUUGGCUCACUGUAACCACUGCCUCCCAGGUUCAAGUGAUUCUCCUGCCUCAGCCUCCCAAGUAGCUGGGAUUAUGGGUGCCUACCACCAUGCCUGGCUAAUUUUUGUAUUUUUAGUAGAGAAGGGGUUUCACCAUGUUGGCCAGGCUGUUCUCAACCUCCUGACCUCAGGUGAUCUGCCUACCUUGGCCUCCCAAAGUGUUGGAUUUACAGGCGUGAGCCACCGUGCCCAGCCUAUUUCUUAUUUUUGUAGAGACAGGGUUUCACCAUGUUGCCUAGGUUGGUCUUAAACUCCUGGGCUCAAGCAAUCUGACUGCUUCAGCCUCCCAAAGUGCUGGGAUUACAGGUGUGAGCCACUGUGCCCAGCUUAUACAGUUUCUAAAGACUCUGGGGUCUCUUAAGGAAGGUCGAGCAACUCAGUAGGUCCUAAGGACACAUCCUUGUAAACAUCAAAACACUAUCAUUUAUAGUGACGUCCCUGGGGCCGGGGCCUGUCGGGGACUCGGGGGCUAGGGGAAGGAUAACAUUAGAAAUACCCAAUGUAGAUGACGGGUUGAUGGGUGCAGCAAACCACCAUGGCACAUGUAUACCUAUGUAACAAACCUGCACGUUCUACACACAUAUCUGAGAACUUAAAGUAUUAAAAAAAAGACAAGAAAAGAAAAGAAAAAGUGCAAUUGUGUUAAUUAAAAAUCAGAUCAUUAUAAUCUGUUUGGAAAAAAAUCCCAGUGGAAUUGUUUAAAAUGUGUGGCUCUCAGAAGUGUAAACCUUCAGCAAUCUAGAAUGACUUAUUCCUCCAAAACUCAGUGUUAUUCAUUUGAAUAUUAAUAAUGGUUGUUUAUUUACUACAUACUAUGUGCCAGACACUGUGUUAACCACUUAUAUGAUCUCAUUUAAUCUGUAAAGCAACUGUAUAUCACCACUGCACAAGUUCAGAAGGACACUGAUGUUCAGAAGGGAUAUGACUCCCCAAGGGUCACCUAGCUUAUAAGGCAAAGCCAGAGUUCAACCCUGGUCCACACCUACACCUGAGACUGUAGACACUUGCCUUUAUGAUUUUGUGGUUGCAGAAAGCCCACAAAUGUCCCAAGUAAUACAUCAGAAGAUGGCAAGGAUGGGGAUAGAAUGAUGGUCAUUGCCCUAGAGGUUGGGCAUGUGGGGCACUGCAGGGACAUUGGGCAGAACCGGACUUUUCUGAGAAACCGGAGAGCAGAAACCCCUGUUGUGCUGUGCAGCCUUGAGCAAAAGACUUGCUUCUCUGUGCUCUGCCUGUUUCUCCAGUGUGUAGGGCUGGGGACACCAUUUCACCUAUUUGACUAUUGUAAGGAGGUGGUUUUUAAUCCCAAGGUGGGGGCUACAUUAAAAGGAGGAUACAUUAAACCGUUAAGGAGAGAGGAAAGUGGGAAAAAGCCACCAGCUAAUUUCGGUUUCCUCACCCCAUGCAGCUAAAAGGUUAUGUGGACUUGUGGUUGAUACCUGUGGGGAUGGGUAUCAUACUCCUUGCUAGAUGCUGCAGAUGCAGGAAUGAAUGUGUCACCAGCUUAGCUCUUGAUAACAAAUGGUGCAUUUCGAUUUUCUUAAAAUUGUGAACAAUUGAAUAAGCAGUGACAUUCUUUGUGGUGUUCAAGGACAGAAUGAACACUCUACUAUUGUUGCAAAAUCAUUUUUUAUACUCCAGAGCAUUCAGAACUAAACCAUUUAACCACGUACUGCUCAGUCUUAGAAAUGACAUUGUGUUGGCUAGGUGUGGUGGCUCAUGCCUGUAAUCCCAGCACUUUGGGAGGCUGAGGAGGGCGAUCACUUGAGGCCAGGAGUUUGAGACUAGCCAGGCCAACAUGGUGAAACCCCAUCUCUACCAAAAAUACAAAAAUUAGCUGGGCAUGGUGGUGCACACCUUUAAUCCCAGCUACUUGGGAGGCUGUGGCAGGAGAAUCACUUGAACCCAGGAGAUGGAGGUUGCAGUGAGCCAAGAUCACACCCCUGCACUCCAGCCUGGGAGACAGAGUGAGACUCUGUCUCAAAAAAAAAAAAAAAAAAAAAAAAAAAAAAGGCAUUAUAUGAUGACAUUACCAAAGUCUAGAGUGAGGCUUCCUGAAUUGGGGCCAAACAGUAGCAUUCCCCUUACAAUCAAUCCACUGGAAAUGCCUCAGAUGCUAAACGACUGGUUUACUUUAAACAUUAGUCUCCACACUGGCAUUUCCUUCUAAGAAAUACAGUUUGCUCUGUUUCUCCUGGAGCUGCUAACCUGAUGCCAUCUGCCUCUGGAUCCAUCAGGCUGCCUGGCAUAUCCAUCUGCAUUUAUAGUUUGGUAGCUAAGGCUCCAUUCUAGCACUUUCAGUGCAGUUGUUUUGCAGAAUUUUUCUUGGGUUCUUUAGUGCUACCCGGCUUCAUUUGAGGGCUAAUUGCAGUAUAAACUUAGCAGUGUUAUUAUCCCCUUUGGUUUAACAUGGUACAAUUAUUAUCAGUUUUUGUUAUUACAACUAAUGAUUAGGUUCUUUACUUGAAUUGAUCUGUCAAAAUGUUCUCUUUUGGAUUUCAGCCUGUUUGAUGUGGAAUGAUGUGGAGUUAUAAGCAAACAAAUGAUGCACUCCUUAAAAUUCUGUCAGGGGUAAUAAAGUGAAUCAAAAUGAAUUCACUGUUUAGCUGUCUUAGCUUUCCUUCCCCUUUUAUCUUGUCAAGCCUUUGACAGCAGCUUCUCUCCCUCACAGAGCAGUUCUGGAGCACUGAGUUUUUGGUUAGAAGGGAUGGGCAGAGGGGUACCUCUGCAAGAUGGAGUGAUUGGAGCAAGAGGAUGGCUGGACUCAUUCUUGGGUACUAGUGUCAAAGGAUCCUAGAGACUUUCUCGUGAAAUGACUUGAUGAUUUAGAAUUGGAAUUGGGGAUGGGAUGGUGGUUUUGGUCUUUCCUGCUGUUCUUUGUCCAAUCAGUUUCUACUGAAACUUCACAGCUAUCCACCUGGGGGCAAACCAGGAUGAAGAAUCAAUGGGCUCCUGGGGAAAAAGCAACAGCAGCCCUCAAUUUUCCAUCAUUUUAGGGAAUGAAAGCCUUUGGAGAAAACAAUUCUGGAUAGCUGAGGCUCAGACAGGAAGCCUGCUUGCUUUAAGCCCUUACUCAAAAUCUUGAGCCCUUACUCAAAACGCACAUUGCUCCGUUUUUGCUGAAUUGCUGGACCUGAUGAAAUCUAUCUUUGAUGACUAAAGAAAUUAUAAGUUUAUUUUUCAAGGGUACCCCUUGGAAGAAUGAUUUUCCUUGCAUGAGCUAAUGAAACAGCAAGUGAAGGAGAUGGGGCUGAAUUUAUGUCCAUGAUUAGCAUGGCCCAUGAACACUGACUUAAAAAAUAAAUCUAGGUGUUUUCUUGAUUCACUUCAAAAAGUUGAGAGCUGGGGACAGGGAGGGAAGGGAGAGGAAACUCCAGAUAAUUAAUGAUCCUUGUGAAAUGGUUUCUGAUUAAUGAGCCUGAGCUAUGGAGUGAUUUAUUUUCCCUGCUCCCUGCUCUUUUUAAUCAAUAAAGAGAUUCUGAUUGGAGGAUUUGCUGAGAGCCCACAUCAUGUAAGUCUCAAGUGUAAUCAGUUUCCCAAGAUUUGCCCUUUUUCUCCAUAUUCAGCUCUACCUGGCGACCACUUACCAGCCUCCUGCGGUGGGCCAGCCCCUGUGACGCACUACCAGGAGUGCAGAGAUGGAUCUACACAGACUGGGCCAAUCAUUACCUAGCCAAAUCCGGCCACAAGCGUCUCAUCAGGGAUCUCCAGCAAGAUGUGACAGAUGGCGUCCUCCUGGCCCAGAUUAUCCAGGUUGUGGCAAAUGAAAAGAUUGAAGACAUCAAUGGCUGUCCGAAGAACAGAUCCCAAAUGAUUGAAAACAUAGAUGCCUGCUUGAAUUUCCUGGCAGCUAAGGGAAUAAACAUCCAGGGGCUGUCUGCAGAAGAGAUCAGGAAUGGAAACCUCAAGGCCAUUCUAGGCCUCUUCUUCAGCCUCUCCCGAUACAAGCAGCAGCAGCAGCAGCCCCAGAAGCAGCACCUCUCCUCACCUCUGCCGCCCGCCGUAUCCCAGGUGGCCGGGGCCCCCUCCCAGUGCCAGGCUGGCACCCCUCAGCAGCAGGUGCCAGUCACUCCCCAAGCCCCGUGCCAGCCUCACCAGCCAGCGCCACAUCAGCAGUCAAAAGCACAAGCUGAAAUGCAGUCCAGACUUCCAGGUCCUACCGCGAGGGUAUCCGCUGCAGGCAGCGAGGCCAAAACACGCGGAGGGUCAACUACUGCUAACAACCGACGCAGCCAGAGCUUUAACAACUAUGAUAAAUCCAAACCAGUCACCUCCCCACCCCCACCGCCAAGCAGCCACGAGAAAGAGCCUUUGGCAAGUUCAGCCUCCUCCCACCCCGGAAUGAGUGACAAUGCACCUGCUUCCUUGGAGAGCGGCAGCAGCUCCACCCCUACUAAUUGCAGUACCUCCUCGGCCAUCCCGCAGCCCGGUGCAGCCACCAAGCCUUGGCGCAGCAAAUCCCUCAGCGUGAAGCACAGUGCCACGGUAUCCAUGCUCUCGGUCAAGCCUCCUGGGCCUGAGGCCCCCAGGCCCACACCUGAAGCCAUGAAGCCGGCCCCCAACAAUCAGAAGUCCAUGCUGGAAAAGCUGAAACUUUUCAACAGUAAAGGGGGCUCAAAGGCAGGUGAGGGGCCGGGGUCCCGGGACACAAGCUGUGAGCGGCUGGAGACUCUGCCCAGCUUCGAAGAGAGCGAGGAGCUGGAGGCCGCCAGUCGCAUGCUCACCACCGUGGGCCCUGCUUCCAGCAGCCCCAAGAUUGCACUCAAGGGCAUUGCCCAGAGGACUUUUAGCCGGGCACUGACCAACAAGAAGAGUUCUCUGAAAGGCAAUGAGAAAGAGAAGGAGAAACAACAGCGGGAGAAGGAUAAGGAGAAAAGCAAGGACCUUGCCAAGAGAGCCUCUGUGACGGAGAGGCUGGACCUCAAGGAGGAGCCAAAAGAAGACCCCAGUGGAGCAGCUGUGCCCGAGAUGCCAAAAAAGUCCUCCAAGAUUGCCAGCUUCAUCCCCAAAGGGGGGAAGCUCAACAGUGCCAAGAAGGAGCCCAUGGCCCCUUCCCACAGUGGAAUACCAAAACCAGGAAUGAAAAGCAUGCCCGGGAAAUCCCCAAGUGCCCCAGCGCCUUCCAAGGAAGGGGAGCGGAGCCGGAGUGGGAAGCUGAGCUCAGGACUCCCCCAGCAGAAGCCCCAGCUGGACGGCAGACACUCCAGUUCCUCUUCCAGCCUGGCGUCCUCAGAAGGAAAAGGCCCAGGAGGGACCACCCUGAACCACAGCAUCAGCAGCCAGACUGUCAGUGGGUCUGUCGGGACCACCCAGACCACAGGAAGCAAUACCGUCAGUGUUCAGCUACCUCAGCCCCAGCAGCAAUACAACCAUCCCAACACUGCCACGGUUGCACCUUUCCUGUACAGGUCUCAGACGGACACUGAAGGGAAUGUUACUGCCGAGUCAAGCUCAACAGGUGUGAGCGUGGAGCCCAGCCACUUCACCAAGACUGGACAGCCUGCUCUGGAAGAACUCACUGGGGAAGAUCCUGAGGCUCGGCGGCUGCGGACAGUGAAGAACAUCGCUGAUCUGCGGCAGAAUUUGGAGGAAACCAUGUCCAGUUUAAGGGGAACUCAGGUUACACACAGCACAUUGGAAACCACGUUUGACACCAAUGUCACCACGGAGAUGAGUGGCCGUAGCAUACUCAGCUUGACAGGGAGGCCCACACCUCUGUCCUGGAGACUGGGCCAGUCCAGCCCUCGGCUCCAAGCAGGAGACGCCCCCUCAAUGGGCAAUGGGUAUCCCCCUCGAGCCAACGCCAGCAGGUUCAUCAACACUGAGUCAGGUCGCUAUGUGUACUCCGCCCCUCUGAGAAGGCAGCUGGCCUCCCGGGGCAGUAGUGUCUGCCAUGUGGACGUCUCAGACAAGGCAGGAGAUGAGAUGGACCUGGAAGGCAUCAGCAUGGAUGCCCCCGGCUACAUGAGCGACGGGGAUGUUCUGAGCAAGAACAUCCGGACCGAUGACAUUACAAGCGGAUACAUGACUGAUGGUGGACUUGGCCUCUAUACCCGUCGCCUGAACCGGCUCCCUGAUGGGAUGGCUGUGGUACGGGAGACCCUGCAACGAAAUACCUCCCUGGGCCUCGGAGACGCUGACAGCUGGGACGACAGCAGCUCCGUCAGCAGCGGCAUCAGCGACACCAUAGACAACCUCAGCACUGAUGACAUCAACACCAGCUCCUCCAUCAGCUCUUAUGCCAACACACCUGCCUCCUCUCGAAAAAACCUGGAUGUGCAGACUGAUGCUGAGAAGCACUCACAGGUGGAGAGGAAUUCCCUGUGGUCUGGUGAUGAUGUCAAGAAAUCAGACGGAGGCUCAGACAGCGGCAUAAAAAUGGAGCCAGGUUCCAAGUGGAGGCGGAAUCCUUCUGAUGUGUCUGACGAGUCCGACAAAAGCACGUCGGGCAAGAAGAAUCCUGUCAUCUCCCAGACAGGCUCAUGGCGGCGAGGCAUGACAGCUCAGGUGGGCAUCACCAUGCCAAGGACGAAGCCUUCAGCCCCGGCAGGCGCACUGAAGACCCCAGGAACUGGAAAAACAGACGACGCAAAGGUGUCUGAGAAAGGAAGGCUUUCUCCUAAAGCCUCCCAGGUGAAGCGCUCCCCAUCAGAUGCAGGCCGGAGCAGUGGUGACGAAUCCAAAAAGCCCCUCCCCAGCAGCUCUAGGACACCUACUGCCAAUGCCAACAGCUUUGGGUUCAAGAAGCAGAGUGGUUCCGCCGCCGGCCUGGCCAUGAUCACAGCCAGCGGGGUGACUGUCACCAGCAGGUCAGCCACACUGGGCAAAAUCCCAAAGUCAUCUGCACUCGUCAGUCGGUCUGCUGGUCGGAAGUCAAGUAUGGAUGGGGCUCAGAAUCAGGAUGACGGGUAUCUAGCCCUAAGCUCCCGGACAAACCUUCAGUACCGGAGUUUGCCGAGGCCCAGUAAGUCCAACAGCCGGAACGGGGCUGGGAACAGGUCUAGCACCAGCAGCAUAGAUUCCAACAUUAGCAGCAAGUCCGCAGGCCUGCCAGUGCCCAAACUGAGGGAGCCUUCCAAAACAGCCCUAGGCAGCUCUCUACCAGGUCUGGUCAACCAAACAGACAAGGAGAAAGGCAUCUCAUCAGACAACGAGAGUGUGGCUUCCUGUAACUCGGUGAAAGUGAAUCCGGCAGCCCAGCCUGUGUCCAGUCCGGCUCAGACCAGUCUCCAGCCUGGAGCCAAGUACCCAGAUGUGGCCUCUCCCACACUCCGCAGACUCUUUGGUGGGAAGCCUACCAAGCAAGUGCCCAUCGCCACAGCUGAAAACAUGAAAAAUUCGGUGGUCAUCUCCAAUCCUCAUGCCACCAUGACUCAGCAAGGUAACCUAGACUCCCCGUCAGGCAGUGGCGUCCUGAGCAGUGGGAGCAGCAGUCCUCUCUACAGCAAGAAUGUGGACCUCAACCAGUCUCCGCUAGCCUCCAGCCCCAGCUCAGCCCACUCGGCCCCUUCCAACAGCCUCACCUGGGGCACCAACGCCAGCAGCUCCUCCGCAGUUAGCAAGGAUGGCCUGGGCUUUCAGUCUGUCAGCAGCCUCCACACCAGCUGUGAGUCCAUCGACAUCUCCCUCAGCAGUGGAGGGGUCCCCAGCCACAAUUCUUCCACUGGCCUCAUCGCCUCCUCCAAGGACGACUCCUUGACUCCCUUUGUCAGAACUAACAGUGUGAAGACCACACUGUCAGAAAGCCCUCUCUCUUCCCCUGCUGCUAGCCCUAAGUUCUGCAGAAGUACUCUGCCCAGGAAACAGGACAGUGACCCGCACCUUGAUAGGAACACUUUGCCUAAGAAAGGACUCAGGUAUACUCCCACCUCCCAGCUUCGCACGCAAGAAGAUGCAAAAGAAUGGUUACGGUCCCAUUCUGCAGGAGGCCUUCAGGACACCGCUGCCAAUUCCCCCUUUUCCUCUGGCUCCAGCGUGACUUCUCCCUCCGGAACAAGAUUCAACUUUUCCCAGCUUGCGAGUCCCACCACUGUCACCCAGAUGAGCUUGUCCAACCCGACCAUGCUGAGGACUCACAGCCUCUCCAAUGCUGAUGGGCAGUAUGAUCCAUACACUGACAGCCGCUUCCGGAAUAGCUCCAUGUCCCUGGAUGAGAAGAGCAGAACCAUGAGCCGUUCAGGCUCAUUCCGGGAUGGGUUUGAAGAAGAAUCAUGGGAGAAAAGUUCUGUGGACAACUUUGUCAGCCGUCUUCACAGCUCACUUCAUUUCUCUCUUCCUUUGUUCCAUCACGCAAGGUAUGAGUUAGUUCAUGGAUCCUCACUCUCCUUGGUUUCCAGCACAUCGUCAGUUUAUUCUACACCAGAAGAAAAAUGCCAGUCAGAGAUUCGCAAGCUGCGGCGGGAACUGGAUGCCUCCCAGGAGAAAGUUUCAGCUUUGACCACCCAGCUGACAGCAAAUGCUCACCUUGUGGCAGCCUUUGAACAGAGUCUUGGUAACAUGACAAUCAGGCUCCAGAGUCUGACCAUGACAGCUGAGCAGAAGGACUCAGAACUGAAUGAGUUAAGAAAAACCAUUGAGCUGCUAAAGAAACAGAACGCAGCUGCCCAGGCUGCCAUUAAUGGAGUAAUUAACACACCUGAGCUCAACUGCAAAGGAAACGGCACUGCCCAGUCUGCAGACCUCCGCAUCCGCAGGCAGCACUCCUCAGACAGCGUCUCCAGCAUCAACAGUGCCACCAGCCACUCCAGCGUGGGCAGCAACAUAGAGAGUGACUCAAAGAAGAAGAAGCGGAAGAACUGGGUCAAUGAGUUACGCAGCUCCUUCAAGCAAGCUUUCGGGAAGAAGAAGUCCCCAAAAUCUGCGUCCUCUCAUUCAGAUAUUGAGGAGAUGACGGAUUCUUCUUUGCCUUCCUCACCAAAGUUACCGCACAAUGGGUCCACAGGUUCCACCCCACUGCUGAGGAAUUCUCACUCCAACUCUCUAAUUUCAGAAUGCAUGGAUAGUGAAGCUGAGACCGUCAUGCAGCUCCGAAAUGAGUUAAGAGACAAGGAGAUGAAGCUGACGGAUAUCCGCUUAGAAGCUCUCAGUUCUGCCCACCAGCUGGACCAGCUCCGGGAGGCCAUGAACAGGAUGCAGAGUGAAAUAGAGAAGCUGAAAGCUGAGAAUGAUCGGCUGAAGUCAGAGUCUCAAGGCAGUGGCUGCAGCCGGGCUCCUUCCCAAGUGUCCAUCUCUGCCUCCCCGAGGCAGUCCAUGGGCCUCUCCCAGCACAGCUUGAACCUCACUGAGUCAACCAGCCUGGACAUGUUGCUGGAUGACACUGGUGAAUGCUCGGCUCGGAAGGAAGGAGGCAGGCAUGUUAAGAUAGUUGUCAGCUUUCAGGAGGAAAUGAAGUGGAAGGAGGAUUCCAGACCACAUCUCUUUCUUAUUGGCUGCAUUGGAGUUAGUGGCAAGACGAAGUGGGAUGUGCUCGAUGGGGUGGUUAGACGGCUGUUCAAAGAAUACAUCAUUCAUGUCGACCCAGUGAGUCAGCUAGGGCUGAAUUCAGACAGCGUUCUUGGCUACAGCAUUGGAGAAAUCAAGCGCAGCAACACUUCCGAAACACCGGAGCUGCUUCCUUGUGGCUAUCUGGUUGGAGAGAACACGACCAUCUCAGUGACUGUGAAAGGGCUCGCAGAAAACAGCCUGGACUCACUGGUGUUUGAGUCCUUGAUUCCCAAGCCCAUCCUGCAGCGCUACGUCUCCCUCCUGAUAGAGCACCGUCGGAUCAUUCUCUCUGGCCCCAGCGGCACUGGGAAAACCUACCUGGCCAACCGGCUGUCUGAGUAUAUAGUGCUUCGAGAGGGACGGGAGUUGACAGACGGGGUUAUCGCCACCUUUAACGUGGACCAUAAGUCCAGCAAGGAAUUGCGCCAGUACCUGUCCAACCUUGCUGACCAGUGCAACAGUGAGAACAAUGCUGUGGACAUGCCCCUCGUCAUCAUCCUGGACAACCUACACCACGUGAGCUCUCUGGGAGAGAUCUUCAAUGGGCUGCUCAACUGCAAGUACCACAAAUGCCCUUACAUAAUUGGCACAAUGAACCAGGCUACCUCUUCGACUCCCAACCUGCAGCUUCACCAUAACUUCAGAUGGGUGCUUUGUGCCAACCACACGGAGCCUGUGAAGGGUUUCCUUGGCCGAUUCCUGAGGAGGAAGCUCAUGGAAACAGAGAUCAGUGGGCGGGUGCGCAAUAUGGAGCUGGUAAAAAUCAUUGACUGGAUUCCCAAGGUCUGGCAUCACCUCAACCGCUUCCUGGAGGCUCACAGUUCCUCGGACGUCACCAUCGGCCCCCGGCUCUUCCUGUCAUGCCCCAUCGAUGUGGACGGCUCGAGAGUGUGGUUCACCGACUUGUGGAACUAUUCCAUUAUCCCCUAUCUCCUGGAAGCCGUCAGAGAAGGACUCCAGCUCUAUGGAAGGCGCGCCCCCUGGGAGGAUCCUGCCAAGUGGGUGAUGGACACAUAUCCAUGGGCAGCCAGCCCACAACAGCACGAGUGGCCUCCCCUGCUGCAGUUACGGCCUGAGGAUGUCGGCUUCGACGGCUACUCCAUGCCUCGGGAGGGAUCGACAAGCAAGCAGAUGCCCCCCAGUGAUGCUGAAGGUGACCCGCUGAUGAACAUGCUGAUGAGGCUGCAGGAGGCAGCCAACUACUCCAGCCCCCAGAGCUAUGACAGCGACUCCAACAGCAACAGCCAUCACGAUGACAUCUUGGACUCCUCUUUGGAGUCCACUCUGUGACAGGGGCCCGGAGCCCAGCGCCCUCCUCUUCUCCUCACCGCAUUCCACCUGCAUCCCCCACAUCACCCUGAAGAUGACUUCCUGAGCCAGCCCCCAGCCACAGCCUUAGAGCUGCGGGAACACCGAGACCCCCCGUCCUUCAGCCUCGACCUGGGUGCAGGCAUCCCGGGCCAGCUGCCUGCGGACCGCUUCCUUCCACAGCGAGAACUGCACUACCUUCUGUUGUACUUUAAUUAUUGUUUUGCCUUGUUGCUGUGACCUCCCUAAGACACUGAAGAUACUUCUCGGGAAAGGAUCAUCGCCGUUGAAAUGAAAAGAGAGACAGAGAGAAAAAAAAAAAGAGAACCCACAUGAAGCUCUGAAACCAAACAGCAUCCUGCCAUGAGCUUCCCAGAGACAGAAGAGACUGGAGCAAAGUCGGAAACACAGAGAAGCACGGCUUCCCCUCAGCACAGACCCUCCAGACUGGGUCUCAGAGCCGUGCCACCCACCCUCCCACACAGCCGGCCACAGGGAGAACUGGUGCUAACCAGGGUGCUUGCUUUGGUCACGUUCAACGCACUACAGAGCUACGACACAGGGAAACCUUAGGAGCAAAUAAACCGUGCUUUCAUGUUUUUUAAAUGGUGCUUUCCUUACCCGAGAGGUAUUUUGCCUGUUCCAAUCAAACCACCCCAUUCAGGUCCAUCAGCCUCUGAUUAAUAUCCGUGAGAGUGAGUGACGGAGUGAGAGUGUGAGCGAGUGGAUGUGGCUGUCAGUGCAGAACAGCAUGUGUCUCUUUCCUUCUGAUAUAUGAAUGAAUCAGGUUUUUUUUUUUUUUUUUCUGCAAACACUGUGUAUAGUGAGACUUGUUCUACUUUGGAGAACAGGUUACCUUUUGAAAAUGAGGUUGAGUUUCUUCCUUUCUGAUGCAUUGAUUUUUGAAGAUUUUUUUUUCCCCCUUCCCCUCUUGGUCAGAAUCAAUCCUUUGGUGAAAGUAAGAACCGCAGGAGUUGAGUUUUGGUUUGGUCCUGCUCAGUUUUGGUUUUUAGUUGUCCAUCCUCACAGUCCUACACACUCGCCUCCUCCUGCUAGGGCUGGGGGUAUCUGUGUCCUUUAAAAUGGAUGAGGACCUGGUCCUCGACAUGUGGGUGAGCCAUGGACCUUGCCUUCCCUUCUCGUCCUUGAGGGUUUAGAACACACACCAACACCUCCAGCGUCCCCGCCCCAGCUUCCGGUGGGGUGAUGCGGUCACCCUGCAAAAGACUUGCACUUUCCUCAGAACCAACAUGACGCAGCUCAAUAAGGGUGAGGGUCACUCCCUCCCAGAAGCCCCGUCUGGACGAGCCUUGCCUGACCUCUUCGGUGCUGACCUUCCCAAAGUGAUGCCUUACUGGUUUUGUACUAACUGUGUUCAUUUUACAUAAGUGUCGUGCCUGCCUGGGGUUUGUUUUUUUUGUCAUUGUUUUCCCCAUUGAAACAAACAGGGCUAAAAAGUCAUCUGUUCAUUAGGAGAACUCAAGUUGCUGUGACUUUUCUCAUCCAAAAGACUCAUUUGUGUGGAUGCGUGACCAUGGGAAAAAGAAAAAAAAAAAGAUCCAUUUUUUAGGUUCUUUUCGGUCUCCAGCUGACAACCCAACUGGACAAUGAUCUGUCUGGUGCAGGAGAAGGCAAAAGUUUCUACAAGUCUACAUGACCUUGCUGAUACUUGUUCUAAUAGAAACCCAGUCUGCUGUGUCUUCAACAUACUGGUAUUUUCAUUACAAAGUAUGGUAAAUUUUUGAGUUGUUUGUUUCUGUUUUGUAAAGAGAAUCCUUAUUGGACACCAGUGAAGGUGUCUCUGUUUUAAUGAUCAGGGUUUUUAUUCCAUCUUUUGCAUUUCUUCUAUUUCUGAAGGUUUGUCUCUUGGCAUCUUUUUUUAGUUUCUUACCAUAAGAGUUUGACCCGAAACUGCUCACUUCACAUUGGAUGACACCAUGUUCUUCCUCUUUGAAAAGAAAAGGGGAAUGUGUCCCACUAGUGAAAGGAAAACUUUUCAACACUAUCCCUGCUUUAGUCUCAGCAAACUCAGACUAUUCUGCUUAGCCUUCAUUAGUCAUCUGGGUGUGAGUGUGUCUUGUUCUGUUUUUCUUUUUAAUAAAACUUUUAAACCAUAUAUUUAGCCUGUGACCAGGGGGGCCAAACCCUAAGAUUUCUGGUAAACCUGAAGGGUGGCCCUCCUCAGACAAUUUAUCUCCCAGCAAUGACCCUACUACACUCGCGUACUGUGAAUUUGGGAGGAGGUAAAGUUGACUUCUCCUCGUGGGCAGUUUUCCAAUCACCUUGUGAGUAGACACCUGCCAAUAUUGUUUGAAACCUUUUUUUAAUAUGACAUCCUCUCUUGUCAUUCUCUUCUCCCCUUUCCCACAGACUUCCCUCCUGGGUCCAGGUUCAGAACCAAGACUUCUGUACCUAGUGCUGCCUGAUUGGUGAACAUUGACUUCAAGUAGCAUAGCCCUUGUGUGACUCACAACUCCGUGUCCUUCCUAAAGUUUCGGGAAGCAGGGUUGUCUAAUAUGCACAUUUCUUAUUUUGGUCAUAUUUUUACUUUAGUGUCACUCACCUUUUACAAAGUGACUUUGUACUCAUUUAGGGCUCUAUCGGAAAUGCUUCCAUUUUGCCUUUUCUACAGUUAGGCCAAUUUUGAAAUAUAUAAAUUCUAUGCAACAUUUAUGUUGAGUUACCAAUGGAAGCCAAAAGUUCUCUUCCCAAACUGCCAAGAAUGAUACAGGCCAUAAUUGAAAUGGGAAUACCUUUUAAGUUUCAUUAGGGGUGGGGUGGGAGUGGGACAGGAACAAGACUUGCCUAGAUCUUUGUUGUAUCUUGGGGACUUUUACUUUGUUGUUUGAUGCUUAAACUUCAAAAUUCUCUGUAUUCAAAUUUGAUUGUGGCGAAUCUACUUCAAAAAGGAAAAAUAAUCCAACUUUGUGGAUAUUAAAUGGAAGGUUUGCUGUUUUGAUCUAGUUGUUUCCAGUGGAGCAGUUUUAUGAAAUAUGUUCUAUAAGAUGUACAUUUUUUCAUUGUAACAUAGAAAUUGUAAAUAAUUGAUUAAAGUGCUGCAUUUUGAUGAAUUUUUUCUAGCCAUUUUUAAAGAGAAAACUAGGAAUUGAGUAUUUUGUGUACGGUAUGUUUCCAUCCUCCCUCCCCUUCCUCCUCCCCUCCUCUCUCUCUCUUCCUACCUAUUUAAUUUUCAUUUGUCAUGAGGUUUUUGGAUUUGCCAAUGAUCUGCUGGACAUCAUGCCCCAUGUCAUAGAGAAUAAAGCUGAUGAUUGUACCAGUCUUAAAUUAUUCAUGAUUCAAUAAAAUUGAUGCUUAUUUAUUCAGA